AGUCUUCAGCUUUCACCGGCUGGGAGUCCGGAGCUGCAGCAGAGGCCACACCCAGGGCUUGGUGGUCCCGCGCUUUCCGGAGCUCAGCAGGCGCUUGCUGCUUGAACCGGUCAAAGAAGGAACGAAUGAAUGACCCUUUUGCCAGGAUGGAGACCCGGGGGCCUCAGGGAGCUGCGAAUCCCAUGGACUCCUCCCGCAGCCUGGGGGACCUCGGGCCUUUUCCGCGGGAGGUAGGGCGCGGGGCUCCGCUAGCUCCGGGCGCCCGGAAUCCCGCGACGGCAGGGGCGAGCCGAAGCCAGGGCGGCGGCCACGAGGACAGAACGGCAGAUCGGGCCCUCGGACCUCGGGCCGGGGAGGAAUUGGACCGUGAGUCCUGGGUCAGAGAGAAAGUGCUCUUUCUCCUGCACCCAGAGAGGUGGUUAGGGACUCGAGGGGACCCUGCACGGGAAGAGGUGGCCGGUGCAGAGGACCUUCCUCAUGCGGGUGGAGAGGACCACGGCGAGGAGCCCAACUACCCUUCUGUCUUUCAACGACAAAAGCGAAUUUCUGGCAGGCGUGUAGCCCCGCCGCGGGACGCAGCAGACCCACCCAAAUACGUGCUUGUGCGGGUGGAGGAUUAUCAGGUAACACAAGAAGUGUUGCAGACCUCCUGGGCCAAGGGUCGCAUGACCACGAGGACUGAGGAGCACUUCGUGACCGCGCUCACUUUUCGCAGCAGUAGAGAGGGACAGCCUGGGGAACGCUGGGGCCCUGCUGAAUCCCGGGCUCUCCAGGCACGAACAGGGGCAUCCCGCGUCCACGCCGCGGGGAGGAGGGUUUCACCGUCUCCAGGGACUUGGCUCGAGGAAAUUAAACUCUAAUGAGUAGCUCGAGAAAUGUUCCGGGAUGGUGGAUGAGCGAUCAUCCUUAAAAGAAAAUGCUAUUCUGGGAGCUCCAACCUGCAAUUAACCUACAGAAGGAACCUUUUGAGAGGCUGGUGCAGCGCUUCGGGGAGGCAGAUUAAGAACUGUAAGCAGCAUAAUACCUCCUUUGUGGCUUGAAUUCCUUCGCUGUCUGGGGACCUAAGUCAUUCAGAAGAGGUGGAGAAAAGAUAUUUUCAGAUUGGCAGAAUGUGGGAGUUUUGAAAUGAGAAAACCUGUUGUUAAUUUGCAUUUUGGAAUAACUCUCAAUUGAUCUCUUUUCUGUUCCCCGCCCCCCUCUUGUUUCUCUUUAGGACCUAGAAACAGAAGUGAAGUUUGAAGUCUGCUCUCUGCAAAGAGGGUGGGAGUGGGUGGAGAAGAGGCUUGUUUUAAAAGCCAAAAACAGAAAGUAAAAAGAAAUGGGAAAGUAAAACCAAAGCAGCAAGUGACUCUCUUCUGAUGUGCACUUUUCAUUUUUCUCCCCCACAUUUCAGUGUUAGAAAGAAAACGAGAGGAGCUAGGGAAAGAAGGAGUUGGGGACAGAAGACUAAGAUUUCAACGUGAAAUUCCAUUUACAAAGGCUUUACUGCAAACAAUAGCUAAUUUAGUCCUGUAAACAUGCAUUUAUCAUACAUUUUAAUUUUAAUAUUAAAAAUACUGCAUGUAAAUGUUCUGAACUAAAGGUAGAUAGCAAUAUGUAGUUUGCCAUAAAAUGAAUGCAUGUCUUAUUCUUUUCCAUAGUUCUUCAUUAAUGAGACUUGUAGUCAAGAAUAGAUUGAAGAUACCAUUCUCCUUGUGUAGUUCAAAAAAAUCUCCUCUGGUAAUACUGAAACAACUAAUUUUUCUUAUUUUGUUUGUUCCUCUUUAUUAUUAAAUACUAUGUGAAUUAACUCUUUAGUAGUUGGCCUGGUUGAAGCUCUGUGAGGAGCAAAGCAGCCCUCUCCAGGUGAACUGCUUGACUUUACCACCUGAAGGAGUAUUUACUGCAAGAAUUAACAAAGCAGACUGCAGUGCAACGGCACGAUCUUGGCUCACCACAACCUCUACCUCCAGGGUUCAAGCGAUGCUCCUACCUCAGCCUCCUCAGUAGCUGGGAUUACAGGCAUGUGCCAUCACCCCGGCUAAUUCUGUAUUUUUAGUAGAGAUGGGGUUUCUCCAUGUUGGCCAGGCUGGUCUUGAACUCCCAACCUCAGGUGAUCCUCCUGCCUCCGCCUCCCAAAGUGCUGGGAUUACAGGUAUGAGCCACCAUGCCUGGCCAAUAUCUUAGGUUUUCUAACUCAUGUUUAUGAGAAGUACUAGAAUCACCUUAAUGUUCCUGAAUUCUGCAAGGCCUCUUGGCUGGAGAAUCAUCACUAGCAGUUCUUAGGCCUGUGAGACCCUCACUUGGGAGAGGAAUUCAGCAUCUGAGCUCAUCUGUGUUCAAAAUUGCUUGACAGGUAGAAAAGAUUCAUCCCUUAAAAUGAAUCUCUUUUCCUUAACAACCCUCCCUGACUCCAGUGGGAGAUUAACUUACUUGGCAUGUAAGUUUCAGACCUGAGCUUAUUAAUUUGGUUGAAUCAUCACAUGUCCCAGGUGACUAAUCAUUGAAUAUAGAGAACAAAAAAAGUCUCUUUCACAAUAACCAAAAAUGGUAAGUAGCAUCACUCAGCUGCCUUCUCUGGAGGCAAUUUCUGGCGUUCAGCUGCUUGGGUUCAAAACUGGCUCUACCUCUUUAUUAACUUGUGUCCUUGGGCAAGUUGCCUUAUCUCUGUGUGCCUCUGUAUCCUGAUUUGUUAAGUGGGGACAAUAAAUAGUAUCAACUUCAUAGAGGGUUUUUUUUUUUUAGGGUUAAGUUAAAUGAAAAUACUUAGAACCCUGCCUGUCAUACAAUAAAUCCUCAAAGUUAGUUACAUUUUUUAUUAUUAGCACGGUUAUUGUUUAGUUCACUUUUCAUCCUAACUAGGCUUUAGUCUUUUGUUUAGUAACAAAAAGCAGAAAUUGUAUAACACAAGAAAGCUAAUGAAAGUCAAGCCGGUGGUUUUUAAUAAGACUCUUCUCUACUCCUGAAAGAAAGGACUUAUUUCUAGCUUUUCCUAACCUUUAAUGGAUCAGUAAGUAUAUUUCUUAAAUUCUUUAGAAAUGACCUUCACAUCUUCUGUAGGGACUCAUGGUAAAGCUCAAAGGACUAAGGUACACUAUCCUUAACAGUCACUGAAAAGAGUUUACAUACCUCCUAGUUCUGGGCAGAUGGGAGCUUUGAAUACUUUCUUUGACCUGUCAGGUUAGUUUGUUUUCCCUCUGGGAUUUUAAAUCUGAUGCCCUGUUGUCUAGAAAAGCAGAAUAGACACAAUUUGUUUUCAUUUUGUCUUUCAGCCAAAAACGUAUUUAGUCAAGUUAGCUUAACUCCUUUAAACCAAAUAUGUUUGAGUUAAUUUUGUUUUGUUUUUGAGACAGAGUCUUGCUCUGUCGCCCAGGCUGGAGUGCAGUGGCACGAUCUCUGCUCACUCCAAGCUCCGCCUCCCAUGUUCACACCAUUCUCCUGCCUCAGCCUCCUGAGUAGCUGGGACUACAUGCGCCCGCCACCAUGCCUGGCUAGUUUUUUUGUAUUUUUAGUAGAGACGGGGUUUCACCGUGUUAGCCAGGAUGAUCUCGAUCUCCUUGACCUUGUGAUGCGCCCGCCUCGGCCUCCCAAAGUGGUGGGAUUACAGGCCUGAGCCACCAUGCCCGGCCUGUUUGAGUUAAUUUUAAGUGAUUUUUUUUUUCCUUUUCUCACUGUUUCAAGCAAUGAAAAUUUAUUUUUAAAGUGCUUACUCAACUUCCCUAUUAACUGCCUAGAACAUGUUUAUAGAUUUCAUUUAAUAUAGAGUUCCUUUUCAUUGGAAACAAAAAGUAGUAAGUCCAAAUACUGUUGAAUUUGCUUCACAGGUGUUCCUGAUCCAAGCAGAACCCUGUUAUUUGAAGAGCCUGAGAAAUCUUAUCCCGUUUACAAAUGUCCUGGGAGUGCAUCCAAAGUGAAACUUGGGUGGAUGAACCGCAUCAAAGACUUCCAGAAGCCACUCCAGUGACCAUAAGAUAAAUGUCAGAAUCGCAUAACCCCCAGGAUCAGCCUGUUGCUCAGGCUGGAGUGCAAUGGCACGAUCUGAGCUCACUGCAACCACCUGCCUCCCGGGUUCAAGCUAUUCUCCUGCCUCAGCCUCCUGAGUAGCUGGGAUUACAGGCGCCUGCAACCACACCCAGCUAAUUUUUGUACUUUUAGUAGAGAUGGGGUUUUGCCAUGUUGGCCAGGCUGGUCUCGAACUCUUGACCUCAGGUGAUCUGCCUGCCUCAGCCUCCCAAAGUGCUGGGAUUACAGGCUUGAGCCACCGAGCCUGGCCUCUACUUUUUAUUACUGUCAUGUAGUUAGUGAUAAAAUGCUUCUAUCUGAAAAAAAAUUUGUUGUUCUAAAUUCUAAAAAAUUCUCGUGAUUAUUGCUUAAAUUUUAAUAAAGCAGAUGUGAUUUUCAAAUUA